CAUCCAGCUCCUCUCCACAGCCCAACCCACACCAGCCUCAGACACCACCAUGACCGGCUCCUGCUGCGGCUCCACCUUCUCCUCCCUGAGCUACGGGGGAGGCUGCUGCCAGCCCUGCUGCUGCCGCGACCCCUGCUGCUGCCGCCCCGUGACCUGCCAGACCACCGUGUGCCGCCCCGUGACCUGCGUGCCCCGCUGCACGCGCCCCAUCUGCGAGCCCUGCCGCCGCCCGGUGUGCUGCGACCCCUGCUCCCUGCAGGAAGGCUGCUGCCGCCCCAUCACCUGCUGCCCCUCGUCGUGCACGGCUGUGGUGUGCAGGCCCUGCUGCUGGGCCACCACCUGCUGCCAGCCUGUGUCUGUGCAGUCCCCCUGCUGCCGGCCCCCCUGCGGCCAGCCGACCCCUUGCAGCACCACCUGCAGGACCUCCUCCUGCUGAGCCACCACCUGCUGCCAGCCUGUGUCUGUGCAGUCCCCCUGCGGCCAGCCGACCCCUUGCAGCACCACCUGCAGGACCUCCUCCUGCUGAGCAGUGCACUGACUGCCCGGAACGCGUAACUCACCUUCUGAAAAAGUCACACUCCCAUUUCUCUACUUUAACAAACCUCCUGCCCUGAGCCCACAAAACCCCACAUCAACCAAGCAGGGAACCGAGCACUGGGCUCAUCUAUUAAGACCUGGGCCAUUCUGAAGUCUGUAAAAGAAGCAAUUUCCUUCUUCUUAAGAUUUCGUGGCAUGUUUAUUUUCUAAUAAAUAUCUGUUCUUUGGCCUUGCAAAAA